CUUCUCCAUCUUCACCUCUUGUCUGUUUACUGCCAUGUUAGCAAUUUGAUGUAUUCAAUCAUGGGUUUUAUAUUCUGUUUGGUGUCCCCCAUUGUUCUCAUCGGAGAUCAGAAGCUUCAGAUGCACUUAUGUCAACUCAAGAGUAGAAUGCUUCCUUAGCUUCCCUCCAGAGUCAGGUUUUGUGUUUCUAGUUCCCAAGUGCACAGCAGGAGUAGUGAUGUCCUCACUGGCUUCUCAUUUGCAUUAAGCUGUGAGCUUCUUUAGCGUGGGGACAGGACCCUGCUCCCAUUGCAUUCUCAGCACCUCACCACACACACCUUGUUUGAGGCCACUCCAGACAGCAUGUGCUGAAGGAUGCCUUGUGGUCAGAAACAAGUUCAUUAACUUUCUCUUUGAAGUGUUUUCGCCCCUGUUUCCUAGCGUUCUGGGAAUUUUACACAUCCUUCCUAUAAAACCAAGUAUCAGGUGAGAUCCUUAGGAUCAGGACCAUGAAUCAAGUGGUGUGAGGGCAACACAGCAAACUUACCCUUUUUAGGCCGUUUCCUUUUUCUGCCCUCAAUCUCUGUGAACUGAACCUUGUUAAAGUCAGUCAACACCAGGGUGGAUGGUUUGCCGUUGUCACCUAUUUUCAGGACAUAACACCCUGACUUAGGAGCCAUUCCGAUCAUUUCUAAUUCAAUAGAUGCGCCCAGCAUUCAGAUUGCCUUUUCUCUCAACCAGGAUCUUUAAAGUCGAUGACAAAAGUUCCAGUCCUGAAUCAUGGCAAAGUGCAGUAGUGAACUGCGGGGUUAUUCUGGAAGGAUCUCUCUAUGGCUGAUGGUCUCAGUUCCGGCAUCAGCCUCUGACUGAGAAUCAGGUCUCACACAGGAGGAGUCAGAUGAGGAGCAAUCCUCUGCUUCCGAUGGAGUUAGUUGUGAUGAAUUGGUGAGGUCUGGUUUUUCACACUGAACUAAAAUGAGCUUUCGCUGUGUCAAGCACAAGACUGACCCCAGAGACACACAUAGUGCACCUCAUAGAAGCUUUUAAUAGUCUUUAUAUUUACUAAAGAAUAGGACUAACUAUGGAACUAUGAAGAUGAGCUGGAAAUGACAGGUGACUUGCCAGCAGGCCAGAGUGUGACUUUUUUUUGUCCCUCAAUGGGAGGUGUCAAUUCUCCCUUCGGUUGUGAGAAUCAGUUGGUUCAUUUGUGGGAAGGUUGCAGGGGGGAUCUUUGAAUCACAGCCUUCAGAUGCCAGAAGGGCAGAGGGAAUCCCACACGGGCUGGUGGAUCAUGUGUGUGCAUUUCUCUCCCUUCUAAUCUGAGGAAACUAAGCGUGAAAGAAUGUGAGCAUGCAGAAAAGGAGAGGCAGGUGUCAGAGGCAGAGGAAAAUGGGAAAUUGGAUAUGAAAGAAAUACACACCUACAUGUGAGUUCAGAAACUGAACCCCACCCUCUUGGGAAACGCCCAUUGGAGUGUUGUUUUUAACCUUUGUACAAUGUUUAGACCCAGUAAAUGCAGAAAUAGAAACAAAUGGUCAGAAGACAUAUCGUGAGAGAGAGAGAGAGUUCACAAAACAGAAAACAAAGUACCUUAAUAUUUACCAGUGACCAAAAGAUGUGAAGUAGCAAAACGGCUCCUGACCCCAUUGCCAGCUAGACUGUGUGGAAACUCGGUUCAUACCAGCCAUUCUAGGGGUGGGGUGAGUUGUUGUCAUCCUUAGGAAAGUGUGUUGUUGUAGGAUCAACCACAUCCUUCAAAAGGACUAUGCCUGUUUAUAAGCCCAGCUGUUUCUGCCCUGUGAAACACGGAAAAUGUUUCAACGUGCGCAAGAGUUGCGGCGGCGGGCAGAGGACUACCACAAAUGCAAAAUCCCCCCUUCUGCAAGAAAGGCUCUUUGCAACUGGGUCAGAAUGGCGGCAGCGGAGCAUCGUCAUUCUUCAGGAUUGCCCUACUGGCCCUACCUCACAGCUGAAACUUUAAAAAACAGGAUGGGCCACCAGCCACCUCCUCCAACUCAACAACAUUCUAUAACUGAUAACUCCCUGAGCCUCAAGACACCUCCCGAGUGUCUGCUCACUCCCCUUCCACCCUCAGCGGAUGAUAAUCUCAAGACACCUCCCGAGUGUCUGCUCACUCCCCUUCCACCCUCAGCUCCACCCUCAGCGGAUGAUAAUCUCAAGACACCUCCCUUAGCUACUCAGGAGGCUGAGGCAGAAAAACCACCCAAACCCAAGAGGUGGAGAGCGGCUGAGAUGGAAUCACCACCCGAACCCAAGAGGCGGAGGGCCGCUGAGGUGGAAUCACCACCCGAACCCAAGAGGCGGAGGGCCGCUGAGGUGGAACCAUCAUCACCCGAGCCCAAGAGGCGGAGGUUGAGUAAGCUGAGAACAGGCCAUUGCACUCAAGCCUGAGCAAUAAGAAUAAAACUGAGUAGAACAAAAUAAAAAAAUCAAAAAACAAAACAAAACCCACACUCCAAAAACAAACUAACAAAGAAUAAAUAAAUAAUAUAAAAAUAAAA